AAAACCAGGGCUCCUAGGAACUGGACUGCUGCUGCCAGUUCUUGACAUUUAGAAAUUAGGAAUUGGCGGAAAAGGAUUAUGGAGACGCCUUGCGCCAAUUUAAAAAGUCUCACCUUAGGUUUGGAAACAAAUGCUUCUUUAUCUUCCUUUGCUACGGUUGAAGUGCUUAACAAGAAACGUUAUUGAUUAUUAAAUGGCAGGCUAGACCAGAGUUGGUAGAUCAGGUUGUCAGAACAAGAAAUGAUUUGUGGUUUUUGAGAGUUUCUGGAGGUGACUGUCAUGUGCUGUAUUAUCUGGGGCUAAUAUUUCAAGGUCUUUCAGGGCAGCUGGCUGUACUGUACCGAUUUAGUGUUUAUUCAGCAAAGAGAUACGAAAGUAUGAAUUUCUCACAGCUCUUCUUUUGAUUUUCUGUUUUUAACAGUUAAGGGGAGUUUGGUUUGGCUGAAGCACGUGGGACACUUCUUUUUUUUGAGUGUAUGAAAAUACUUUUACUUCCUCUCGAGUUUUCUAAAUUUGCUUUUUACUGUUUCAUUUCCUCCAUCUUUUUGCUUAGUUUCCUUGUUUAAUUUUUUCGAUUCCCUACCGUAUUAUUGUGGUGAGAAUUAACUCUUAUUUUCAGGGUUAAUCGCUGCCCCUAAAGCCCAGACAAACCUACUUUUCUGUUAUUUGCAGGAAAAUUAAAGAAAUAAUGCUGAGAGGAAGGUAGACGUGUGGUAAUGGCGGCUGAUGUUUCAAGGAACAGUUUACAAGCACAUGAUAAUUUCUUAGCUGAGAAAACAGAAGUCCUUAGUGAAGAUCUAUUACAGAUUGAGAGACGCCUGGACACGGUGCGGUCAAUAUGCCACCAUUCCCAUAAGCGCUUGGUGGCAUGUUUCCAGGGCCAGCAUGGCACCGAUGCCGAGAGGAGACACAAAAAACUGCCUCUGACAGCUCUUGCUCAAAAUAUGCAAGAAGCAUCGACUCAGCUGGAAGACUCUCUCCUGGGGAAGAUGCUGGAGACGUGUGGAGAUGCUGAGAAUCAGCUGGCUCUCGAGCUCUCCCAGCACGAAGUCUUUGUUGAGAAGGAGAUCGUGGACCCUCUGUACGGCAUAGCUGAGGUGGAGAUUCCCAACAUCCAGAAGCAGAGGAAGCAGCUUGCAAGAUUGGUGUUAGACUGGGAUUCAGUCAGAGCCAGGUGGAACCAAGCUCACAAAUCCUCAGGAACCAACUUUCAGGGGCUUCCAUCAAAAAUAGAUACUCUAAAGGAAGAGAUGGAUGAAGCUGGAAAUAAAGUAGAACAGUGCAAGGAUCAACUUGCAGCAGACAUGUACAACUUUAUGGCCAAAGAAGGGGAGUAUGGCAAAUUCUUUGUUACGUUAUUAGAAGCCCAAGCAGAUUACCAUAGAAAAGCAUUAGCAGUCUUAGAAAAGACCCUCCCCGAAAUGCGAGCCCAUCAAGGCAGCCCACUAAACCCGCUGGCGUGUGUUGAUGAAGUGUGGUGCAGGUGCAGCGUGCCACUGCAGCUUCUGGGCAGCCUGAGUUGGUGCCAUCUAGAUAAGUGGGCGGAAAAACCAGCCUUUGGGACUCCCCUAGAAGAACACCUGAAGAGGAGCGGGCGCGAGAUUGCGCUGCCCAUUGAAGCCUGUGUCAUGCUGCUUCUGGAGACAGGCAUGAAGGAGGAGGGCCUUUUCCGAAUUGGGGCUGGGGCCUCCAAGUUAAAGAAGCUGAAAGCUGCUUUGGACUGUUCUACUUCUCACCUGGAUGAGUUCUAUUCAGACCCCCAUGCUGUAGCAGGUGCUUUAAAAUCCUAUUUACGGGAAUUGCCUGAACCUUUGAUGACUUUUAAUCUGUAUGAAGAAUGGACACAAGUUGCAAGUGUGCAGGAUCAAGACAAAAAACUUCAAGACUUGUGGAGAACAUGUCAGAAGUUGCCACCACAAAAUUUUGUUAACUUUAGAUAUUUGAUCAAGUUCCUUGCAAAGCUUGCUCAGACCAGCGAUGUGAAUAAAAUGACUCCCAGCAACAUUGCGAUUGUGUUAGGCCCUAACUUGUUAUGGGCCAGAAAUGAAGGAACACUUGCUGAAAUGGCAGCAGCCACAUCCGUCCAUGUGGUUGCAGUGAUUGAACCCAUCAUUCAGCAUGCCGACUGGUUCUUCCCUGAAGAGGUGGAAUUUAAUGUAUCAGAAGCAUUUGUACCUCUCACCACCCCGAGUUCUAAUCACUCAUUCCACACUGGAAACGACUCUGACUCGGGGACCCUGGAGAGGAAGCGGCCUGCUAGCAUGGCGGUGAUGGAAGGAGACUUGGUGAAGAAGGAAAGCUUUGGUGUGAAGCUUAUGGACUUCCAGGCCCACCGGCGGGGUGGCACUCUAAAUAGAAAGCACAUAUCCCCCGCUUUCCAGCCGCCACUUCCGCCCACAGAUGGCAGCACCGUGGUGCCCGCUGGCCCAGAGCCCCCUCCCCAGAGCUCUAGGGCUGAAAGCAGCUCUGGGGGUGGGACUGUCCCCUCUUCCGCGGGCAUACUGGAGCAGGGGCCGAGCCCAGGCGACGGCAGUCCUCCCAAACCGAAGGACCCUGUAUCUGCAGCUGUGCCAGCACCAGGGAGAAACAACAGUCAGAUAGCAUCUGGCCAAAAUCAGCCCCAGGCAGCUGCUGGCUCCCACCAGCUCUCCAUGGGCCAACCUCACAAUGCUGCAGGGCCCAGCCCGCAUACACUGCGCCGAGCUGUUAAAAAACCCGCUCCAGCACCCCCGAAACCGGGCAACCCACCUCCUGGCCACCCCGGGGGCCAGAGUUCUUCAGGAACAUCUCAGCAUCCACCCAGUCUGUCACCAAAGCCACCCACCCGAAGCCCCUCUCCUCCCACCCAGCACACGGGCCAGCCUCCAGGCCAGCCCUCCGCCCCCUCCCAGCUCUCAGCACCCCGGAGGUACUCCAGCAGCUUGUCUCCAAUCCAAGCUCCCAAUCACCCACCGCCGCAGCCCCCUACGCAGGCCACGCCACUGAUGCACACCAAACCCAAUAGCCAGGGCCCUCCCAACCCCAUGGCAUUGCCCAGUGAGCAUGGACUUGAGCAGCCAUCUCACACCCCUCCCCAGACUCCAACGCCCCCCAGUACUCCGCCCCUAGGAAAACAGAACCCCAGUCUGCCAGCUCCUCAGACCCUGGCAGGGGGUAACCCUGAAACUGCACAGCCACAUGCUGGAACCUUACCGAGACCGAGACCAGUACCAAAGCCAAGGAACCGGCCCAGCGUGCCCCCACCCCCCCAACCUCCUGGUGUCCACUCAGCUGGGGACAGCAGCCUCACCAACACAGCACCAACAGCUUCCAAGAUAGUAACAGACUCCAAUUCCAGGGUUUCAGAACCGCAUCGCAGCAUCUUUCCUGAAAUGCACUCAGACUCAGCCAGCAAAGACGUGCCUGGCCGCAUCCUGCUGGAUAUAGACAAUGAUACCGAGAGCACUGCCCUGUGAAGAAAGCCCUUUCCCAGCCCUCCACCACUUCCACCCUGGCGAGUGGAGCAGGGGCAGGCGAACCUCUUUCUUUGCAGACCGAACAGUGAAAAGCUUUCAGUGGAGGACAAAGGAGGGCCUCACUGUGCGGGACCUGGCCUUCUGCACGGCCCAAGGAGAACCUGGAGGCCACCACUAAAGCUGAAUGACCUGUGUCUUGAAGAAGUUGGCUUUCUUUACAUGGGAAGGAAAUCAUGCCAAAAAAAUCCAAAACAAAGAAGUACCUGGAGUGGAGAGAGUAUUCCUGCUGAAACGCGCAUAGGAAGCUUUUGUCCCUGCUGUUAAUGCGGGCAGCACCUACAGCAACUUGGAAUGAGUAAGAAGCAGUGCGUUAACUAUCUAUUUAAUAAAAUGCGCUCAUUAUGCAAGUCGCCUACUCUCUGCUACCUGGACGUUCAUUCUUAUGUAUUAGGAGGGAGGCUGCGCUCCUUCAGACUUGCUGCAGAAUCAUUUUGUAUCAUGUAUGGUCUGUGUCUCCCCAGUCCCCUCAGAACCAUGCCCAUGGAUGGUGACUGCUGGCUCUGUCACCUCAUCAAACUGGAUGUGACCCAUGCCGCCUCGUUGGAUUGUCGGAAUGUAGACAGAAAUGUACUGUUCUUUUUUUUUUUUUUAAACAAUGUAAUUGCUACUUGAUAAGGACCGAACAUUAUUCUAGUUUCAUGUUUAAUUUGAAUUAAAUAUAUUCUGUGGUUUAUAUGAAAA